AUGGAUUUUCUAUUCUUUUACUUCAUUUUUCUUUUUGUCACUCCUGCUCCAUGUUAAACACCUUGGGAGGCUGUUAUGCACAUCAGGAUGGAGUUGGUUUCUAAGAGCCUGGUCUCUGAUGACGCAGACUGAGUCUUGAAUGGUCAGACCACUGUCCUGUGCUGGGGCUGUGUCAGGCCCUUCCCAGAGACUCCCACGUGUCCCCUCAUGACACUGCCUCUGCGUGGGUGACAAGGGAAUGGACCGCCACCCUCCCACACACCCCAUGCCCUUGGUUCUGCCCAGCCCUUUACCAACCUCACUCUUGGGCAGGCCUCAUGACCGCUCUGCCCCUGCAUUGCGGCUUUGGUGAACAAGCCUAGAGAAGGUGUGCCUCAGGCUGAGCAUCACACAGCAAGACAGGGCUUAGUCUGGUGUUAGGACCAAAGUUUCUUCUCCUCCUCGUCUUUUUAUUUUUUAAGAUGUGGUUGGAAGCCCGGGCUGCAUGGGGACAUGUGGAAAACAGGCACCUGAGAGUGUGGCUCCCGCGCCCUCAUGCCUCACAAGCUCCUCCAGGCUGUUCCAGGUGUGGGGCACUGUGUGUUCCAGGUGUGUGGGGCCAUGACGCGCCCUUGGGGCCUGCCCGCAAGGAGCCAUCGUUGUUGAGGGGCAGGACGCAGCUAAUAGAACGAUGUCCCACUCCCGUGAGCUUAGGAGCCCAAAUCAGCUACAAUGGAAGUGGCACUGGCUUCAGUUACAGAAAACCUGACGAAAUCCAAUGAGGCAGACCCAUAAAGGGAGCAGGGGCUUGUUCUCCCCAUGGUGAUGAGUCUGACGGUGCCAUUGGGGCACCAAGGCAGCUGCUCACAUCCUCAGCUUGGGACCCUGCCCCUUGCUGGCCACAUGGCUGCUGUCCUCGGGAUGCCGUGCCCACACUUCAGGCUGGAGCCAGGAGAAAGGAAGACUGUCAGUGAGGUGGGUGGCCACAGCUGCCCCUUCCAAAGGACCAGGAGGCUCGAUUGUGCCUCCUGCAGUCAUCCCCUGGGCAAACAGUGUCACAGCUGGCCCAGCUGCUGGUGAGGCUGGCUACAUUGAUGCCUUGAACAAAACUGGGGUUCUGUUGCUAAGGGACAAAGGAGGCCUGGGUAAUAGUGAGGGCGGCUCGGCGGGGUUGGUGGGUGCAGGAAUCAAGGACUGAGUGCCCGUGGGCUUUGCUGGAGCAGAAGCUGUGCUGGGAGCAGAGCAGGAGGUGCACAGGCCUUCUCCUGUCCAGGCAGGGGCUGCAGGGGAGCAAGGGAUGGUCUCCUGAGCAGGUGACAUUGAAGCCAGGCAGCAGAGGGUAGAGAGGAAGGGUGGGAGGGUGGGGAAACUCACGACAAAGCCAUAGGUUGACACUGACCUGGAAAUUCAGCUUAAACCCUGAGAAGUCCAUGCUACUAUUCAGAGAGGGAGCAUUUCUGAGGUUGGCUUUAGUGGGUGCUGCCUCAACGUUCCUUCCGAAGGCCUUGGAACCACCCCCUAACCUUGUUGCCCACAUUCCCUCUGGGACCUGGAAUGGUAGAUCCAAUUUGGGGGGUGCCAGCUGAGGACCAGGCAACCCCCACCCCCUUAGGUAACAGAACUCAGCGUCCUGGGGCCAAUCCCACUUAUUCACCCUGUUGGUCUCACUGGUUGGCCAAGGGGUGGGACCAGAGUUCUUCCCAGGGAGUCCUGCUUCUCUGGAGGAAGGAGGGAGCCCAGAGCUGCCCGAGGUCAUGUGAUGACCUCUUCCAGGGAGGGGCAGAGAUGAGGGAAGGGAGGGGAGCCCCGGCCCUAGGCCCAGGCAGCUAUUGGCUAUUUCCCUCAUCCCUUCCUGAGGACCCCUUAGCAUCCUCCUCCCCCUCCCCAUCGGCUCAGCCUGAGGGAGUGGGCUCCUGGCUCUUCCACGGAGAGGUUUACCUUCCCUGACUUGCUGUGGGGCACUCAGGCGGGCUCAUCCCAGAUUUCGGAGGAGCCAACAGGUACGGAGCCCCUCCUCUGGUGGUUCCUACCCACGCUAGACCAUUCCCCCUGCAGUGUCCAGGCACAGAAACAGCCCCAUAUACGCCUUGUAUGGUCAAGAAAGCGGCUCCUGGAGGUGGUCUGCCCUGGGAGGAAAGGGCUUCACUUUCCCCUCCUUUGCACACCUGAACACGGAGCUGUCAGAGGAGGCUGAGUGAGGUGGCGGCCAGACAGACAGCGCCAGCCACGGAAGGGGAGGUGGGCACCGUGCCAGGCACCCGGCAUCCUCAGUCCAGACUGACAGCUCUCAGACAGGCAUUGGUCCUGGCGAACCUUCCCCUUCAAGUGGAAGCUGGGGGGUCAGCAGUCAUGGGCAUCCUCCCUGGUUAGGAGCCGGCUUCCCUGCACUCUAGCUGUCCUAGCCGAAGAGUGAAGCCCUGUCCAAAUCAUGGCGAGGCUGCAAGACAGGCACACACUACUGCCUCCUGGGAGCCCAGGGGAGACUGAAAUACACCAAGGCAAGGAGCGUGGGUGGGCCCAGGACAGGCCGGCCUGAGCACCAGCCCAGGAAUGCUGGUGGGCAUGUGCCCCUCUUCCCUCCCACCCAUGUGUGCACACAUUUGUGCCAUAUACUACCGUUCCCAUGUUUGCGCCUGGGCACACACUUGUGCCAGCAUACACACACUUGUGCACUUGCACCUGGUGUCCAGGAACACUCCCUCAGCUCACAGACGUGCGCUGUGUGCACACAGUACCACGCAGUGUCCACGAGCACACUUUUGUGUUCGUGUUCACAGAACCCGUGUGCGCACACAUGCACAGUCCUGGGCUGCAGAGAACCCCAGCCAGCGGGGCGGUGGGGGAAGGGGAGGGCACGCCUCCUUCCCAGGAGCUCAGCAAGGCUGUCCGCGGGAGCCCAGGGCUGCCCGCAGGGCUUUGGCGUAGGCCUCGCAAGCACAGCAAGCAUCACAGAGUGAGGGCGGCGGGAGAACCUCCGCUUGCCGGAGAAGGUGCAGCGGACUCAUCACUCUUGCUCUCCUGCCUUGGGUGUGACUCUUGGUUCACCUCUGGGGAAACAGGCUGAAAGGUGACCCUGGCGGCCCAAGGACACACACCCAUUGUCCGCAGGUUCCUCCCAGGUGUCUUCUCCAGCAGGUCACCGGGAGAGCGAGGGGCUGGAGUCUUUCGGGAGCUCAGUGCCCGCAGGCAGAGCAGGGAAAGGGAGGCGCCCCAGGCCCCUGCGGAAGGAGGUCCCAGGAGGGUCUCCGCAAGGGGCUCCCUACUCUGCACUUCAGCUCCUCCAGGGAGGGGCUGCGACCUCGGGCAAAGGUCCCUCAGAUGUCUUGAGACUCAGUUUCCUCGUUGGUGACACUGGGAGUCCGGAGUCCCCGCGGGGCCUGCCAGCCCCCGGCCGAGCACGGCCCCACGCGGAGCCCGUGCAGCCUGACUUGGGGCCCAACGCCCGUCCCCGCAGCGCGAGACGCGCAGGUGCCCGGCCCUGCCCUGGCCGAGACCCGCCGCCUGCGCAGCCCCGCAGAAGCUCCAGCUUUGGCCCGUGUGAGGUCCGGGCUCGGCCUGGGCUGGGCGGAGCCCGCUCCCGAAGCGCCUCAGCGCCGGGCCGCCGCCCUCCACGUGACCUCCACCUUCGCCGUCAUCCCCAUAUGCAAAACGGGGAAACGGGGAAACGGAGGCCCACCACCAGGCAACUCAGUGUGGAGGCUGCUGGCCCUGCCAUCUGUAAGAAGAUGUCAUACGGAUCCAUCGCCCGUGGAGGUGGCCUGGGGAGCCGUGGCCCUUUCGGGGGACCUUCGAGACAAGGCUGUCAGCCCCUAGAGUGCGCUAGAUGUUGGACCGAGUAUGGAAUCCGCCAUUUCCCCUGCCCGUCGCCAGAGAGCAAGCUGCAGAACCGCUGUGUGGGGAAGGACGGGGAAGGUGAUCUGGGGCCAGCAGGCACGCCUAUUGUCCCAAGGGCCAGGAAGCGAGGGCCUGGGGUUGCCCCUGAAGGCAGCCGGAUGCCGGAGCCCACCUCAUCACCCACCAUUGGCCCGAGGAAGGACUCGGCUGCUGGGCCCCAUGGCCGGAUGGCGGGGCCCAGCACUACCCGGGCCAAGAAGAGGAAGCCCAACUUCUGCCCGCAGGAGACCGAGGUGCUGGUGUCCAAGGUGAGCAAGCACCACCAGCUGCUGUUUGGCACGGGGCUGCUGAAGGCCGAGCCCACUCGCAGGUACCGCGUGUGGAGCCGCAUCCUGCAGGCCGUGAAUGCGCUGGGCUACUGUCGCCGCGACGUUGUGGACCUGAAGCACAAGUGGCGGGACCUACGAGCCGUCGUGCGGCGCAAGCUGGGCGACCUCCGGAAGGCGGCCCAUGGCCCCAGCCCUGGUUCCGGCAAGCCCCAGGCCCUGGCUCUCACGCCCGUGGAGCAGGUGGUGGCCAAGACCUUCUCUUGCCAGGCCCUGCCCUCCGAGGGCUUCAGUCUGGAGCCGCCCAGAGCCACCCAGGUCGAUCCGUGCAACCUCCAGGAGCUGUUCCAGGAGAUGUCGGCCAACGUCUUCCGAAUCAACUCCAGUGUGACCUCCUUGGAGCGGAGCCUUCAGUCCUUAGGGACACCGAGUGACACGCAGGAGCUUCGGGACAGCCUGCACACGGCACAGCAGGAGACCAACAAGACCAUUGCAGCCAGCGCCAGCUCCGUGAAGCAGAUGGCCGAGCUGCUGCGCAGCUCCUGCCCGCAGGAGCGUCUGCAGCAGGAGCGUCCUCAGCUGGACCGGCUGAAAACCCAGCUCUCAGAUGCCAUUCAGUGCUAUGGAGUGGUGCAGAAGAAAAUUGCAGAAAAGUCCAGAGCGCUGCUUCCCAUGGCGCAGAGGGGCAGUAAACAGCAGAGUCCCCAGGCCCCGUUUGCCGAGCUGGCUGAUGAUGAGAAGGUCUUUAACGGGAGUGACAACAUGUGGCAGGGCCAGGAGCAGGCGCUGCUCCCGGACAUCACUGAAGAGGACCUGGAGGCCAUCCGGCUGCGGGAGGAGGCCAUCCUGCAGAUGGAGAGCAACUUGCUGGAUGUGAAUCAGAUCAUCAAGGACUUGGCCUCCAUGGUGUCAGAGCAAGGAGAAGCUGUUGGAGAAGCCCUACCCUUUUGCUGCUGGAGGCCACCCAUCAAGGACCUGACAGGCGAGAGGGUCCAGCAGCAGCAAAGCCAUCUGCCAGCAGAGCUGCAGCCCCGAGCCGGCCGCGGCAGCCCUGCUGCUGGGUGCCGGGCCGGGCUCCACACCCCUGCGGCCGGGCCCCCACUCCCGCACCAAGACACGCAAGCCCAACUUCAGCCCCCAGGAGACGGAGGUGCUGGUGCAGAGGGUGCGGCGCCACUACCCGCUGCUGUUCGGGGCGCUGCGGGGCACACCUGCCCGAAAGCACCGCGUGUGGAGCCGCAUCCUGCAGGCAGUGAACGCGCUGGGCUACUGCCGCCGCGACCUGGGGGACCUCAAGCACAAGUGGCGGGACCUGCGAGGUGCUGUGCGCAAGAAGCUGGCGGAGGGCGGCCCCGCCCCCGGCCUCCUCCUCACACCUGUGGAGCGCAUGGUGGCAGAGACCUUUUCUGCCCACGGUCCCCAAGGCGAGGGCCAGACCACGGAGCCCCUGCCAAGCCUCGUCUGCAGCCCGCAGCUGCCACUGGCUCCAAGGGUGACGCUGGCUCUGAGGGUGAUGCUGGCUCCGUGCUUCCUCCUGCCGCCUCCGUGCCUCCUCCCACCGCACCUCCUCUCCUCCUCAAGACACCGUGCCAGGAGCUCCUUCGCCGUCCUCCGCAUAUGGUGGCACACCCUUCGAAGCAGAGCCCCGCUGGACCCUCCCCUUCCUGGGAGCUGCUGGAAGGACUUUGGGAACGAAGCCCCGGAAGCAGGACCAGCUCCUUGAGGGCCACAGAGUGGACAGAAGGACCCAGCCUCACAGGACAGGCAGGGGCUGGCCUCAAACGCCCCCAGUGGCAGCCAUGGCAGAACUUGGAGCGCUGGGGCAUCCUCAGCUGCUCCUGCUCACAGCGGUGCAUGAGGCUGGGACCCAUGGGCAGAGUGGGCCGGACUGGUUGGGAGACGCAUGUAGACCCAGCCAACCCUGUGGCUGGGCUUGGACAAGGGGCCUGGGCUGUGGGCCUUGGGCGAUGGGCCUGGGCACUAGGCCUUGUGGUGGGGCUUGGGGGAUGGGCCUGGUCAGUGGGCCUCCUGAUGGGGUGGGGCUGGAGGAGGAUCUGGGUCCUCUCAGGCCUGUGCAGGCCAGGGAUGGCUGGAUCCACCCCCAUUGAGGCCACAUUGUCUCCUGAAGGGCAGAUUCUUGCAGCCAAGGGUCCUAUGGGCAGAGGCAGACCUGGUUUGGGGGUGCUUCAUGGCAAGGAUAGACAUGUGGUGUGGGGCUGAGAAGGAGGGGCCUGGCAGGGGUGGCACUGGUGUGGCCCAGGUGCUUAGUCCUUUUCUGCAAGUCCUCAGCCCUGGAGGCUGCAGGAACUCAGGUUUGCUCACCCUGUGGUUCCCUGCCCUAGACUGAGACCCAGCCUCGACUUCUGUGACCCCUGGUGGAUCAGCCACUCCAGGUCCCCAGGCCGCUGGGCUCCCCUGCAGCACGGGAGUCUUUGGUGCCUGUGAGCUGCUUUGAGUGGCCUGCCCUGCUGCUGACAGCAACUGACGUGUUGAAUUCCCAAGCGAGAGUGCUUAGGACAGGGCCAGACUUCCUCUUGUGGGCGCAGAGGCAGGAAGUAGGAAAGUGGCUGCCAAGCCUGAGGACAGGGUGGGGGCAUCCCAGCUGCAGGCCCAGUUGCCCCGAGCCGGCCAUGCUUUCCGCUCUGCAGCGGCACUGCCUGGGGUUUGGGCAGGGCCAGGCCUGCAGGGCUGGUCACGGCUGUGGGGCUGGGGGCAGCGAGUUGACCCAGUGCAGGGGGGUCUCCCACAGGGGUCCCUGUGCCCUGAGGGCACUGGGCAGGCAGUUUCCUUUGAGGUGUGUGUGCUGCUCUGCGAGUGUCUGGGGAGGGCGGUCCCAAAGGCUGCUCUCUCUGGCCCCUGGAGGCCUCUGGCCUAGUGCUUGGGUAUCCCUUGGACUCCUGGAGUCAGGGGAUGUGCAAGGGGCCCCCGUGGAGCACCCCCUGUGUUGGGAGGAGCAGGUGCCCAGGGCCUGUGGCUCUGCAGGGCUCACCUCACAGACUGGGGGCCUCCAAGACCUGACAAAGCCACUGGGCCCAGGGCUGAUGGCUGAUGAGGUAUUGGAGUGUCGCUCAGUACCACAGGUCCCACGCACCAAACCUGUCCUCACCCCACGAGCAACACGCGGCCGCACAGCACCGGGAGCAGCCCCCCUCCCCUUGUGCAUCUCUGUGCACUGCGCCGGGGCAGGACAUGGCGUGCCCACCUGGCAGCCUGGGCGCUGAGGGAGAUGUUGCUGGCUGCGGAGCUGGGCAGUGGUUGUGUGAGGUGUCUUGAAUGUGGGCAGUGCCAUGCUGGCUAAGAAUGCCCCUGGGACCGCCCUGGGUCUGUGGCCGGUGCAUGCAGCCCUGGAGCAGCAGGACAUCAGUCCCCAUUCUGAGGGUGGGCCUCCAGGUCACACACUACGAUCAGAGUCCCCAGGGCCAGGGCUAGGUGUAGAGCAGGAUUGGGCACAGGCUGAGUCCAAGGGUGGGGUCCAGGGCUUGGCUGAGGCUGCGUGUGGUCACGGGGCAGAGAAAGUGUCCAGCCAGGGCACAUGGCCUGUCCAGCACCACCUGUGUUAGCCCAGACCACCAUGGCCUUCCUGUCUCUGCUGGCAAAUGCUCUCCACUGUCCACAUUCACCUCUCAGCAACAGAAGCGAGGCCAGGCUGUUACCACUGCAGGUGUAAGGUGGCUCCUUUGCACGUGAGCGGGGCAUUGCCCGGGCCCAGGCUAGCGCCUCCUCCCUGGCAGGCUGGUCCCUCCUGAGUGGCAAUUGUGGGGGGAUCCGUCACACCUCUGGCCCCAUCUUCCUUCCCUCUCCUCCUCCAUUGGCUCAGAGGGUCGUGACCCUAAUGUGGCAGGACAUAGAGAGCAGAGUUCAGUUGGGGGCUGUCUGCAAGUGAGCAAAGGGGUGCUUUGCUCCAGGAGCGGCCGAGGCCGUCACCCAUACCCGCUCUCUGGGCUUUGGCUCCUUGUGCAGGAGCCUGGCUCUCCCCUCCCUGGCUAGGGCAGGAGCCCCCAGAUGCGGCGAUCAGGGUGUGUCUGCGAGUGCCUGCGGCUCCACUAGGGCCCUGCGCUGGGGGCAAGGGUGGGGUGGAGCUGGUGACCAAGGGUUCAAGGAUCCCUGUGAGGCCUGGGUGGGGGCUUCUGAAGGCAGGGCUCAUGGGUUCCACCUCCUGCCCAGGGGGCUUGCAGAGAUGGGGCCACAGUUCCCUGAUGAGAGUAGGGAGUCCUUGCUGGGACGGUGGGGAGUGGCCUUGUCUUUCUGAGGACCCUCCUCCCUCAGAGCCAGUCGUGCCAGGCUGUGCCUGGCAGCAGUCCCUGUGGUUGUAAUGGCCUCUCUAUCCCAGGCCUUAAGACCCCUGAGGCUCAAGUCAGCUCAGGUCUGUGCCCUGGUAGGCACUGCAGGUGCACAGUUUGUUUAGAUACUCCUGCCUCCCAAGCUCUUCUCCAGUUGCCUGAUUGGAGGCAGGCCUUGCAAGGAACCUCCCUCCGGGAAGAAGGCUUGCCCGUGCUCGUGUUUGCUCGUGUUUGCAUGUGGCUCUGUUGAGGACCCCGGCUGUGCCUGCGCUCCUGGUGCCCAGGUGGCAUGUGUCCUUCCUUUGGGUGGAAGACAAUGCUGAGCAUGGAAUCUUCCGGAUCCCUGGGGCUGCCCCGGCCCUGGUCUGGUGUCUCCCGUGGGCCCUGCUGAUGUGGCUUCCCUGGGUGGCACUGCUGCAGCCACCGAGCCCGGCUUUUCCCAGGUACCAUCUCCCGUGAUCCCCGCACGGCAGCACAACUUUCUGAUCAGCUCCCUGUGCUUGAGUCGAGGGCCAGUGCGUGUGGCAAACCAGAGCCCUGUGCUUGCAGACCCGGUCUCCAUCAGCCGCGUCGCAACUCCACAGACGUUAAGGCAGGGGCUUUGCCCCUUCAGAGGGGGCCGUGGCCACAGAGUGGAGGGGCUGGCCCAGGCAAGGUCAUGACAGAGCAGGACUUGACCCCAGCCCUCACCUCCGCCUGCCACUCCCACCCUUUCCUGAGUGGACUCUUCCUGCCCCACCUGGUGUGGGCACUGAGGAGUCCCCUUCCCUGGGCCACCUCCAGGCCUCCGUUCUAAUGUCAUUGCUGCCCACUGCCCACACCACGCGGAGCCCUCGGCACGUCUGGCAGCCCAGCGCCCAUCCCUGCAGCCUCUGCUCCUCUGCAGGCCCUGGGCUCAGGCUCCCUGGGCUUGCCUUUGGGGGGUGUCCUCAGGGCGGGGGCGGCUGGGCCUCCAUCUGUAAUUGCCUUCUGUUGUCUUGAU